AAAGAGGCUGAGUACCCCAGCAACUGCUUCUUGUCGAAAGCCAUUUCCUAUCCUCCGCGCUAGGCGUCUCACAGGCUUUUCCCCCAGUCAAAUCAAUGCUAAUAAUCGGAAAUAGCAAGUUCUGAGAAACGCUAGCGUAGAAUGGGCGCACUAGGGGUAAGGGGAUGGGCCCCAGACUUCAGCAGCCGUUCUGGGAAGUUGCUCGCCUUUUUCGAAGACUCUAGCUGCAAAACUGGAAGCCGUCGGUGGGGCAAGGCAGAGAAGAGACCACGUCUGGCGGAUGAGUCCUGUGAUUAUCAGGUCACCUGGGUAACGCCCAACCACGACGGGCUGGGUCUCAGCGCGAGGCCUGCAGCCCGGCGCCGACUGGAAUCCCCAGCACUGCCGUCUGGAGGACAUCGGCGGUAUCUCCCCAAGAGACGGGAAGUCUGUGUGUCGAAGAGGCGCGGGACGCAAGCCCACCAACCUGGCCGACCCCAGGGAAAGGCCGAGCGUCCAGCCCGCGGGGGCCCAAGAUGGUGCCAGAGUUCGAGGCCCUCUGUGCAUGCACCCCGCCCGCCUUCGAAUCUAGCCUGUUCGCCGUUGUGGUUUGUCCUCCCGGUUCCUCUGAAGGAGUUGGUCAGUAGAACCAUGGCCUCCAUUGACUACGUCCUCAGAGUCGCAGCUCUCUUCAGUCGAGCUCCAGUCACAGAGGACGGUUGUGGUGAGACCCAGGCAGAAGUAUUUCCGGUCAACGAGGUCGCGGGUAGUGCGCAUGCGCUUCGUGCAGGGCCCUGCGCAAGGGCGCCUGGGAAACCUUGCGAGAAGUGACACACGCCCUGUCCUCAGGGAGCCCACGGCCGACUGGGAAACAGGAGAACGGGUCAAACGUGGGACGUCCGUCAGCUAUACCGAAAGUUCACUCCAACCAGGAUUUGCUGCCACUCUACAAAAUCUUCUCAAGAUCAACAAUACCCUCUGCCUGACCAACAUGGUGAAACCCCGUCUCUACUAAAUACAAAAAAUUAGCUGGGCCUGGUGGCUCUUGCCUGUAAUUCCAGCUACUUGGGAGGCUGAGGCAGGAGAAUCGCUUGAACCUGGGAGGCAGAGGUUGCAGUGAGCCGAGAUUGCGCCCCUGCACUCCAACCUGGACAACACAGCGAGAUUC